AAAAGGCCCAAGAGGAUGGGAUACAAAGAGCCUUUGGACCGCUGAACUUGUGGAAGUUCUAAGAAAGAACACAGGCAUACACAGGAAGAUACAUUCACAGAAAGAGCUUCCUGCACAAAGUAAGCCACCAGCGCAACAUGACAGUGAAGACCCUGCAUGGCCCAGCCAUGGUCAAGUACUUGCUGCUGUCGAUAUUGGGGCUUGCCUUUCUGAGUGAGGCGGCAGCUCGGAAAAUCCCCAAAGUAGGACAUACUUUUUUCCAAAAGCCUGAGAGUUGCCCGCCUGUGCCAGGAGGUAGUAUGAAGCUUGACAUUGGCAUCAUCAAUGAAAACCAGCGCGUUUCCAUGUCACGUAACAUCGAGAGCCGCUCCACCUCCCCCUGGAAUUACACUGUCACUUGGGACCCCAACCGGUACCCCUCGGAAGUUGUACAGGCCCAGUGUAGGAACUUGGGCUGCAUCAAUGCUCAAGGAAAGGAAGACAUCUCCAUGAAUUCCGUUCCCAUCCAGCAAGAGACCCUGGUCGUCCGGAGGAAGCACCAAGGCUGCUCUGUUUCUUUCCAGUUGGAGAAGGUGCUGGUGACUGUUGGCUGCACCUGCGUCACCCCUGUCAUCCACCAUGUGCAGUAAGAGGUGCAUAUCCACUCAGCUGAAGAAGCUGUAGAAAUGCCACUCCUUACCCAGUGCUCUGCAACAAGUCCUGUCUGACCCCCAAUUCCCUCCACUUCACAGGACUCUUAAUAAGACCUGCACGGAUGGAAACAGAAAAUAUUCACAAUGUAUGUGUGUAUGUACUACACUUUAUAUUUGAUAUCUAAAAUGUUAGGAGAAAAAUUAAUAUAUUCAGUGCUAAUAUAAUAAAGUAUUAAUAAUUUAAAAA